AGUUGCGCUUCUGGCGAUGGCGAUCAGAGGUCCUGCUGCGCUCUCCGCCGCGCUCUACCUCCAUUAGCCGCGCUGCGCGGUGCUGCGCCCUCGCCGGUGCCUCUCUCCUGGGUCCCAGGAUCGGCCCCCACCAUCCAGGCACGACCCCCUUCCCCGGCCCCUCGGCCUUUCCCCCAACUCGGCCAUCUCCGACCCGGGGCGCGUGUUCCCCCCGGCCCGGCGCCUUCUCUCCCUCCGGGGGCACCCGCUCCCUAGCCCCGGCCCGGCCCUCCCCGCGGCGCAGCACGGAGUCUCGGCGUCCCAUGGCGCAACCUACGGCCUCGGCCCAGAAGCUGGUGCGGCCGAUCCGCGCCGUGUGCCGCAUCCUGCAGAUCCCGGAGUCCGACCCCUCCAACCUGCGGCCCUAGAGCGCCCCCGCCGCCCCGGGGGAAGGAGAGCGCGAGCGCGCUGAGCAGACAGAGCGGGAGAACGCGUCCUCGCCCGCCGGCCGGGAGGCCCCGGAGCUGGCCCAUGGGGAGCAGGCGCCCGGUGCCGGCCACGACGACCGCCACCG